GGGCGGGGCCAAGAUGGCGCCGAGCGCCGGGUGAGCAGCGUCUCGGCUGCCGCUAGAGUUUUCCUGCUCCCCGCGCUCGGGUGGCGGGGGCGGGUCUGAGUGGUACCCCGGAGGAGACCCUUUGAAGGUCCCUUGUGGGGACUGGAAAGAGGACGGUUGGUUGUGUGUCUGUGCUCGUGGGGACCCCGUGUGUGUGCCUGCAUUGGAGAGAUGUUGCAGGAGAUGGGGUGGGCUCUCUGAACCUCCUUUCGCGCUGCCCGGGGAUCUUCGACCUGCUUCUCUGCUGGGAUCUCGCUUAAGUUAACCCUUCCCUGGGACGCCUUCCUGCCGCCUCCACUGAUCUGAGGAGAUCCUGUGACUGUAGCGUGUUUUAUGAGCCUUUACUGGCAGAGGGUACCGCCGGGUAUUGAAGGAUUCGUAGGAGUUCGCCAGGGAAGUGGGACACGACCCCCUCUUGUAAACCCGGCGCCAGGCACAGAGGUUUCCGUCUGUUACCCAGGCUGUUGUGCAGUGGCACCAUCUUGGCUCACUGCAGCCUCCAACUCCUCAGUUCAAGCGAUCCUCCUGCCUCAGCCUCCUAAGUAGCUGGGAUGACAGGUUCACACCACCAGGGUCUCCGUCUCUCCACCGGGGGCUUCAUCCUUCCAGGGAGGAGAAGAGGGACUCCAGAAUGGCUGAGGAGAAGAAGCUGAAGCUUAGCAACACUGUGCUGCCCUCGGAGUCCAUGAAGGUGGUGGCUGAAUCCAUGGGCAUCGCCCAGAUUCAGGAGGAGACCUGCCAGCUGCUAACGGAUGAGGUCAGCUACCGCAUCAAAGAGAUCGCACAGGAUGCCUUGAAGUUCAUGCACAUGGGGAAGCGGCAGAAGCUCACCACCAGUGACAUUGACUACGCCUUGAAGCUAAAGAAUGUCGAGCCACUCUAUGGCUUCCACGCCCAGGAGUUCAUUCCUUUCCGCUUCGCCUCUGGUGGGGGCCGGGAGCUUUACUUCUAUGAGGAGAAGGAGGUUGAUCUGAGCGACAUCAUCAAUACCCCUCUGCCCCGGGUGCCCCUGGACGUCUGCCUCAAAGCUCAUUGGCUGAGCAUCGAGGGCUGCCAGCCAGCUAUCCCCGAGAACCCGCCCCCAGCUCCCAAAGAGCAACAGAAGGCUGAAGCCACAGAACCCCUGAAGUCAGCCAAGCCAGGCCAGGAGGAAGACGGACCCCUGAAGGGCAAAGGUCAAGGGGCCACCACAGCCGACGGCAAAGGGAAAGAGAAGAAGGCGCCGCCCUUGCUGGAGGGGGCCCCCUUGCGACUGAAGCCCCGGAGCAUCCACGAGUUGUCUGUGGAGCAGCAGCUCUACUACAAGGAGAUCACCGAGGCCUGCGUGGGCUCCUGCGAGGCCAAGAGGGCGGAAGCCCUGCAAAGCAUUGCCACGGACCCUGGACUGUAUCAGAUGCUGCCACGGUUCAGUACCUUUAUCUCGGAGGGGGUCCGUGUGAACGUGGUUCAGAACAACCUGGCCCUACUCAUCUACCUGAUGCGUAUGGUGAAAGCGCUGAUGGACAACCCCACGCUCUAUCUAGAAAAAUACGUCCAUGAGCUGAUUCCAGCUGUGAUGACCUGCAUCGUGAGCAGACAGUUGUGCCUGCGACCAGAUGUGGACAAUCACUGGGCACUCCGAGACUUUGCUGCCCGCCUGGUGGCCCAGAUCUGCAAGCAUUUUAGCACAACCACUAACAACAUCCAGUCCCGGAUCACCAAGACCUUCACCAAGAGCUGGGUGGACGAGAAGACGCCCUGGACGACUCGUUAUGGCUCCAUCGCAGGCUUGGCUGAGCUGGGACACGAUGUUAUCAAGACUCUGAUUCUGCCCCGGCUGCAGCAGGAAGGGGAGCGGAUCCGCAGUGUGCUGGACGGCCCUGUGCUGAGCAACAUUGACCGGAUUGGAGCAGACCAUGUGCAGAGCCUCCUGCUGAAACACUGUGCUCCUGUUCUGGCAAAGCUGCGCCCACCGCCUGACAAUCAGGACGCCUAUCGGGCAGAAUUCGGGUCCCUUGGGCCCCUCCUCUGCUCCCAGGUGGUCAAGGCUCGGGCCCAGGCUGCUCUGCAGGCUCAGCAGGUCAACAGGACCACUCUGACCAUCACGCAGCCCCGGCCCACGCUGACCCUCUCGCAGGCCCCACAGCCUGGCCCUCGCACCCCUGGCUUGCUGAAGGUUCCUGGCUCCAUCGCACUUCCUGUCCAGACACUGGUGUCUGCACGAGCGGCUGCCCCACCACAGCCUUCCCCUCCUCCAACCAAGUUUAUUGUAAUGUCAUCGUCCUCCAGCGCCCCAUCCACCCAGCAGGUCCUGUCCCUCAGCACCUCGGCCCCCGGCUCAGGUUCCACCACCACUUCGCCCGUCACCACCACCGUCCCCAGCGUGCAGCCCAUCGUCAAGUUGGUCUCCACCGCCACCACCGCACCCCCCAGCACUGCUCCCUCUGGUCCUGGGAGUGUCCAGAAGUACAUCGUGGUCUCACUUCCCCCAACAGGGGAGGGCAAAGGAGGCCCCACCUCCCAUCCUUCUCCAGUUCCUCCCCCGGCAUCGUCCCCGUCCCCACUCAGCGGCAGUGCCCUUUGUGGGGGGAAGCAGGAGGCUGGGGACAGUCCCCCUCCAGCUCCAGGGACUCCAAAAGCCAAUGGCUCCCAGCCCAACUCCGGCUCCCCUCAGCCUGCUCCGUGAUGCUCCACCUGCCAGCCCCCGGAUUCCCACACAUGCAGACAUGUACACACGUGCACGUACACACAUGCAUGCUCGCUAAGCGGAAGGAAGUUGUAGAUUGCUUCCUUCAUGUCACUUUCUUUUUAGAUAUUGUACAGCCAGUUUCUCAGAAUAAAAGUUUGGUUUGUAAGUUCUGA